GUUGAUGUCCUGCAUCUAACGCGGUGUAACCCCCGAAGCCGAGCGAGCUCCGGAGGAAUUUCAGUAUCUGCUACGGUAACUUCAUCAGCCCGCCAAGAUGGCGAUGCAAGCGGCCAAGAGGGCGAACAUUCGACUUCCACCUGAAGUAAAUCGGAUAUUGUAUAUAAGAAAUUUGCCAUACAAAAUCACAGCUGAAGAAAUGUAUGAUAUAUUUGGGAAAUAUGGACCUAUUCGUCAAAUCAGAGUGGGGAACACACCUGAAACUAGAGGAACAGCUUAUGUGGUCUAUGAGGACAUCUUUGAUGCCAAGAAUGCAUGUGAUCACCUAUCGGGAUUCAAUGUUUGUAACAGAUACCUUGUGGUUUUGUACUAUAAUGCCAACAGGGCAUUUCAGAAGAUGGACACAAAGAAGAAGGAGGAACAGUUGAAGCUUCUCAAGGAGAAAUAUGGCAUCAACACAGAUCCACCAAAAUAAAUGUUUUCUACAUUUUCAUUUGGACUAAAUCCCACGAAUGACAACUACCACCUUUUUUUCCUUUUUAAUUAAUACUAAAUAUUGUGAUUUCUUAUUUGAGGUUCAAAAUGACCUGCUUGAAACUUUGAUACAUAUUGGAAUACAUUAUGUUAAUAAACUUGUAGCUUUUUGUGAAA